ACUCGGCACUCACUGCCCGGGCCGCCCGGACAGGGAGCUUCGCUGGCGCGCUUGGCCGGCGACAGGACAGGUUCGGGACGUCCAUCUGUCCAUCCGUCCGGAGAGAAAUUACAGAUCCGCAGCCCCGGGAUGGGGCCGGCCCCGCUGCCGCUGCUGCUGGGCCUCUUCCUCCCCGCGCUCUGGCGUAGAGCUAUCACUGAGGCAAGGGAAGAAGCCAAGCCUUACCCGCUAUUCCCGGGACCUUUUCCAGGGAGCCUGCAAACUGACCACACACCGCUGUUAUCCCUUCCUCACGCCAGUGGGUACCAGCCUGCCUUGAUGUUUUCACCAACCCAGCCUGGAAGACCACAUACAGGAAACGUAGCCAUUCCCCAGGUGACCUCUGUCGAAUCAAAGCCCCUACCGCCUCUUGCCUUCAAACACACAGUUGGACACAUAAUACUUUCUGAACAUAAAGGUGUCAAAUUUAAUUGCUCAAUCAGUGUACCUAAUAUAUACCAGGACACCACAAUUUCUUGGUGGAAAGAUGGGAAGGAAUUGCUUGGGGCACAUCAUGCAAUUACACAGUUUUAUCCAGAUGAUGAAGUUACAGCAAUAAUCGCUUCCUUCAGCAUAACCAGUGUGCAGCGUUCAGACAAUGGGUCGUAUAUCUGUAAGAUGAAAAUAAACAAUGAAGAGAUCGUGUCUGAUCCCAUCUACAUCGAAGUACAAGGACUUCCUCACUUUACUAAGCAGCCUGAGAGCAUGAAUGUCACCAGAAACACAGCCUUCAACCUCACCUGUCAGGCUGUGGGCCCGCCUGAGCCCGUCAACAUUUUCUGGGUUCAAAACAGUAGCCGUGUUAACGAACAGCCUGAAAAAUCCCCCUCCGUGCUAACUGUUCCAGGCCUGACGGAGAUGGCGGUCUUCAGUUGUGAGGCCCACAAUGACAAAGGGCUGACCGUGUCCAAGGGAGUGCAGAUCAACAUCAAAGCAAUUCCCUCCCCACCAACUGAAGUCAGCAUCCGUAACAGCACUGCACACAGCAUUCUGAUCUCCUGGGUUCCUGGUUUUGAUGGAUACUCCCCGUUCAGGAAUUGCAGCAUUCAGGUCAAGGAAGCUGAUCCGCUGAGUAAUGGCUCAGUCAUGAUUUUUAACACCUCUGCCUUACCACAUCUGUACCAAAUCAAGCAGCUGCAAGCCCUGGCUAAUUACAGCAUUGGUGUUUCCUGCAUGAAUGAAAUAGGCUGGUCUGCAGUGAGCCCUUGGAUUCUAGCCAGCACGACUGAAGGAGCCCCAUCAGUAGCACCUUUAAAUGUCACUGUGUUUCUGAAUGAAUCUAGUGAUAAUGUGGACAUCAGAUGGAUGAAGCCUCCGACUAAGCAGCAGGAUGGAGAACUGGUGGGCUACCGGAUAUCCCACGUGUGGCAGAGUGCAGGGAUUUCCAAAGAGCUCUUGGAGGAAGUUGGCCAGAAUGGCAGCCGAGCUCGGAUCUCUGUUCAAGUCCACAAUGCUACGUGCACAGUGAGGAUUGCAGCCGUCACCAGAGGGGGAGUUGGGCCCUUCAGUGAUCCAGUGAAAAUAUUUAUCCCUGCACACGGUUGGGUAGAUUAUGCCCCCUCUUCAACUCCGGCGCCUGGCAACGCAGAUCCUGUGCUCAUCAUCUUUGGCUGCUUUUGUGGAUUUAUUUUGAUUGGGUUGAUUUUAUACAUCUCCUUGGCCAUCAGAAAAAGAGUCCAGGAGACAAAGUUUGGGAAUGCAUUCACAGAGGAGGAUUCUGAAUUAGUGGUGAAUUAUAUAGCAAAGAAAUCCUUCUGUCGGCGAGCCAUUGAACUUACCUUACAUAGCUUGGGAGUCAGUGAGGAACUACAAAAUAAACUAGAAGAUGUUGUGAUUGACAGGAAUCUUCUAAUUCUUGGAAAAAUUCUGGGUGAAGGAGAGUUUGGGUCUGUAAUGGAAGGAAAUCUUAAGCAGGAAGAUGGGACCUCUCUGAAAGUGGCAGUGAAGACCAUGAAGUUGGACAACUCUUCACAGCGGGAGAUCGAGGAGUUUCUCAGUGAGGCAGCGUGCAUGAAAGACUUCAGCCACCCAAAUGUCAUUCGACUUCUAGGUGUGUGUAUAGAAAUGAGCUCUCAAGGCAUCCCAAAGCCCAUGGUAAUUUUACCCUUCAUGAAAUACGGGGACCUGCAUACUUACUUACUUUAUUCCCGAUUGGAGACAGGACCAAAGCAUAUUCCUCUGCAGACACUAUUGAAGUUCAUGGUGGAUAUUGCCCUGGGAAUGGAGUAUCUGAGCAACAGGAAUUUUCUUCAUCGAGAUUUAGCUGCUCGAAACUGCAUGUUGCGAGAUGACAUGACUGUCUGUGUUGCGGACUUCGGCCUCUCUAAGAAGAUUUACAGUGGCGAUUAUUACCGCCAAGGCCGCAUUGCUAAGAUGCCUGUUAAAUGGAUCGCCAUAGAAAGUCUUGCAGACCGAGUCUACACAAGUAAAAGUGAUGUGUGGGCAUUUGGCGUGACCAUGUGGGAAAUAGCUACGCGGGGAAUGACUCCCUAUCCUGGGGUCCAGAACCAUGAGAUGUAUGACUAUCUUCUCCAUGGCCACAGGUUGAAGCAGCCCGAAGACUGCCUGGAUGAACUGUAUGAAAUAAUGUACUCUUGCUGGAGAACCGAUCCCUUAGACCGCCCCACCUUUUCAGUAUUGAGGCUGCAGCUAGAAAAACUCUUAGAAAGUUUGCCUGACGUUCGGAACCAAGCAGACGUUAUUUACGUCAAUACACAGUUGCUGGAGAGCUCUGAGGGCCUGGCCCAGGGCUCCACCCUUGCUCCACUGGACUUGAACAUCGACCCUGACUCUAUAAUUGCCUCCUGCACUCCCCGCGCUGCCAUCAGUGUGGUCACAGCAGAAGUUCAUGACAGCAAACCUCAUGAAGGACGGUACAUCCUGAAUGGGGGCAGUGAGGAAUGGGAAGAUCUGACUUCUGCCCCCUCUGCUGCAGUCACAGCUGAAAAGAACAGUGUUUUACCGGGGGAGAGACUUGUUAGGAAUGGGGUCUCCUGGUCCCAUUCGAGCAUGCUGCCCUUGGGAAGCUCAUUGCCCGAUGAACUUUUGUUUGCUGACGACUCCUCAGAAGGCUCAGAAGUCCUGAUGUGAGGAGAGGUGCGGGGAGACAUUCCAAAAAUCAAGCCAAUUCUUCUGCUGUAGGAGAAUCCAAUUGUACCUGAUGUUUUUGGUAUUUGUCUUCCUUACCAAGUGAACUCCAUGGCCCCAAAGCACCAGAUGAAUGUUGUUAAGUAAGCUGUCAUUAAAAAUACAUAAUAUAUAUUUAUUUAAAGAGAAAAAAUAUGUGUAUAUCAUGGAAAAAGACAAGGAUAUUUUAAUAAAACAUUACUUAUUUCAUUUCACUUAUCUUGCAUAUCUUAAAAUUAAGCUUCAGCUGCUCCUUGAUAUUAACAUUUGUACAGAGUUGAAGUUGUUUUUUCAAGUUCUUUUCUUUUUCAUGACUAUUAAAUGUAAAAAUAUUUGUAAAAUGAAAUGCCAUAUUUGACUUGGCUUCUGGUCUUGAUGUAUUUGAUAAGAAUGAUUCAUUCAAUGUUUAAAGUUGUAUAACUGAUUAAUUUUCUGAUAUGGCUUCCUAAUAAAAUAUGAAUAAGGAAGGAUAUGUUGAACUUACUUGAGACUUGAAAGACAGUGGUCGGCAGCGGCCUUGUGGCCUUUGCAAAGGAAUUCCCUUAAUGCCUGGUCCUUGGGGCAAUUGCUCUGACCAUUCUUGGCAUUGCUUUAUAGAGAUAUGGAAAAACCACACCAGGGUCUGUAGAUAAGGAAUAAAGAAUAUUGAAGGAUUGAAAAA